CCCCGCUGGAGAAAUUUGCGCCCAGAGGGUGCGGGGCCGCCCUGGCCGUCCCGCCCGUGGGCCCGGCGCCCUUCUCGGAGCCCAGCCAUUCCGCUAGACCCGAACUAGGACUGGUAGGAGGGGUGAUCGGCCCAACCUCAGGCCCCAGCCGCGGGCCGGGAAGGCUUCCCCACGGACGAGGGGCAAGCCCCUCGACGUCAGGGUGUCGUCUAUGUAGAGGGGAAUCUGCCUCCUCUCAAAGGGGAAUUCUUUCAGCGAGUCAAGCCCGUCUGAUUCGGGGCUGACUCAGGGCAGAGGCCCAGAGAGGACCUGGAUAGGUUGCGAGAAGUCGAGAUCAGAGGGGGCGGAAGGCAGUGAGAAAAGGGAGACGAGCAUCGGGGGGUGAGAGACAAACUCAGGUCUGGCUCUUGGCCCUUGACGCCACUGAAUUCGCUUCCCACGGUGGGAAGAGGAGAAAAGGGCCCUGACACCGCGGCUCGCCAGGGGCCCGCUGCGUAGCUGCAUCCCGAUCCCGCUGAGGGGACAGCAAAUAGUGAAGUGCUGAUAGCUUGUGGUUGUCGUUACACUGGAAGGAAAUAGAAAACCGGACAGUGGUGUGUGUGUGUGCGUCUUGGCCAAAGGAACUUCUUGGGCUGGGUUAAUGUGAGCAGGUACUCCCUUGGGCGAAGUACUGGCACUGGCCAACGGCCUUUCCCUCUGGCCGUCUCCGAGGAAGCAGAGCUGCUGUGAAGACAGUUCCUCUCGCCACCGUGUGUUCAGUUCUGACCUUGAAGGUUUUGGAGGUCUGUUGUGAAGAUAUUUAGCCUAUGAAAGUCCUGGUGAUCUGAAGGACAGAUCAAUUUACUGCUCUAUUUCCUGGAGCUGUGAUACCUUUAAAAAAAGUAUUUUGGGUCGGGCAUGGUGGCUCACGCCUGUAAUCCCAGCACUUUGGGAGGCCGAGGUGGGUGGAUCACCUGAGGGUCAGGAGUUUGAGACCAGCCUGACCAAUAUGAUGAAACCCCCGUCUCUACUAAAAAUACAAAAAUUAGCCGGGCGUGGUGGCAUGUACCUGUAAUCCCAGCUACUAGGGAGGCUGAGACGGGACAAUCACUUGAACCCGGGAGGCGGAGGUUGCAGUGAGCCCAGAUCGCGCCAUUGCACUGCAGCCUGGGCAACAAGAGCGAAACUCCAUCUCAAAACAAAAUAAAGUAUUUUGGUUAUCACAUGGAGUCUUAGAGAUUCACAACAAAUAACCCAUAGUGCACCCUUAGCCAUGUUGACUUAGUACAUUGUGUGGUCAUUGUUAGGGUCGGUGACAUAAUAAACGAAGAACCAUUGUUCAUUCCCGAAGGUGUCAUUACCCGGCAAAUAUUUAUGUCUUCUGGGCCGGGGUCAUGGCUCACGCCGGUAAUCCCAGCACUUUAGGAGGCGAGGUGGGUGGAUUACUUGAGGUCAGGAGUUCGAGACUGGCCUGACCAACAUGGUGAAACCCAGUCUCUACUAAAAAUACAAAAUUAGCCGAGCGUGGUGGCGCACGCCUGUUAUCCCAGCUACUCGGGAGGCUGAGGCAAGAGAAUCGCUUGAACCCGGGAGGCAGAGGUUGCAAUGAUCCGAGAUCGCGCCAUUGUGCUCCGGCCUGGGCGACGAGUGAAACUACGUCUCAAAAAAAAAUUUUUUUUAUGUCUUCUGGCCAUGUUAGCAGAGUAGAAGAGUCCACCGGGCAUACUUAGUAUCUUUGGACAAAUAGGAAUUCAAUGAAAACGUAUUCUUAAAGGCGAAAAAGGUGGAUUUGCUAGUGUUCACACCCUUUCCAGAAAUUCUUGGCUGGUAACCGCGAAACCGACUGGAGCAGGAGCUGGGAGAACUGGAGAAAACUGCUCUAAUCUCACUUGACUCCAGCUAGGAGCUGAUGCUGCAUCGUAAUAACAUUUGCAGAGCGCUUUCACAGGCGCUGGAGUGACUUGUCUGAGAUUCCUCCAGAACUGAGCCCUUUGUUGGAACCAUACCCCAGCCCAUGGUCCCAUGACUAGGUGGAUAGUACUCCUUGUACCUCCUGCAACCCAGAACCCUGGCUGACCACUUUGAAGGAGGAUGCUCCAGCAGGUCAAUGGCCACAAUCCGGGGUCUGAUGGCCAAGCCAGGGAGUACCUCAGAGAAGACCUGCAGGAGUUCCUGGGUGGGGAGGUCCUGCUGUACAAACUGGAUGACCUCACCAGGGUGAAUCCUGUGACACUAGAGACAGUCCUGAGGUGCCUGCAGGCCCGGUACAUGGCAGACACAUUCUACACCAAUGCUGGCUGCACCCUGGUAGCCUUGAACCCCUUCAAGCCUGUUCCUCAGCUCUACUCGCCCGAGCUAAUGAGAGAGUACCAUGCUGCGCCUCAGCCCCAGCAAUGUGGUCAUUCAGAGUCUGCUAGUGCCACGGCCUGCCCAAUAGGAGCUGGCAGAAUUUUGAACCAUGAAGAACUGACUACAGGACAGAAGAAACUGAAGCCCCAUGUGUUCACUGUGGGUGAACAGACCUACAGGAAUGUCAAGAGCCUGAUUGAACCAGUCAACCAGUCUAUUGUUGUCAGUGGAGAGAGUGGUGCUGGAAAGACAUGGACGUCUCGCUGCCUAAUGAAGUUCUAUGCUGUGGUGGCCACCUCACCUGCAUCUUGGGAGAGCCACAAGAUUGCAGAGAGGAUAGAACAGAGGAUCCUGAACUCCAACCCUGUCAUGGAAGCUUUUGGGAAUGCGUGUACACUGAGGAAUAACAACAGCAGUCGCUUUGGGAAGUUCAUCCAGCUCCAGCUGAACAGGGCUCAGCAAAUGACUGGAGCCGCAGUCCAGACCUACCUCCUAGAGAAAACUCGAGUGGCCUGCCAGGCUUCCAGUGAGAGGAACUUCCACAUCUUCUAUCAGAUUUGCAAAGGAGCCAGUGAGGACGAGAGGCUCCAGUGGCACCUUCCUGAGGGAGCUGCCUUCUCCUGGCUGCCCAACCCAGAGAGGAGCUUAGAAGAGGAUUGUUUUGAGGUGACCAGAGAGGCCAUGCUCCAUUUGGGCAUUGACACCCCUACCCAGAACAACAUCUUUAAGACUGCCCCAGAGCAGCAGGAGGGGAUAGAUAGGAUGGCCUGGCAGUCGAGAAAGGGAGGCCACUUCAGGGAGGUAGCAAUGCAGUGGAAAGUGACCCUCACCUCCAGAUGGGGGCUGCUCAGACACUGCCAGGUCCUAGCUGGACUGCUGCACCUUGGCAAUAUCCAGUUUGCUGCCUCCGAGGAUGAAGCCCAGCCCUGCCAGCCGAUGGAUGAUGCCAAGUGUGAGGACUCUGUCAGGACGGCAGCCUCGCUGCUGGGGCUCCCAGAGGACGUGCUGCUGGAGAUGGUGCAGAUUAGAACCAUCAGGGCAGGCAGACAGCAGCAGGUGUUCCGGAAGCCCUGCGCCCGAGCCGAGUGUGACACCCGUAGAGACUGCCUGGCCAAACUGAUCUAUGCGCGGUUGUUUGACUGGCUGGUAUCAGUGAUCAACAGCAGCAUCUGUGCAGACACCGACUCGUGGACCACUUUCAUAGGCCUGCUGGAUGUGUAUGGAUUUGAAUCAUUUCCUGACAACAGUCUGGAACAGUUGUGCAUCAACUACGCCAAUGAGAAGCUGCAGCAGCAUUUUGUGGCUCACUACCUAAGGGCCCAGCAGGAGGAAUACGCAGUUGAGGGCCUGGAGUGGUCAUUCAUCAACUACCAGGACAACCAGCCCUGUUUGGAUCUCAUUGAGGGAAGCCCCAUCAGCAUCUGCUCCCUCAUAAAUGAGGAAUGCCGCCUCAAUCGACCCAGCAGCGCAGCCCAGCUCCAGACACGCAUUGAGACUGCCCUGGCAGGCAGCCCCUGCCUGGGCCACAAUAAGCUCAGCCGGGAGCCCAGCUUCAUUGUGGUGCAUUAUGCGGGGCCUGUGCGGUACCACACAGCAGGCCUGGUGGAGAAGAACAAGGACCCUAUCCCACCUGAGCUGACCAGGCUCCUGCAGCAAUCCCAGGACCCCCUGCUCAUGGGGCUGUUUCCUACUAACCCCAAAGAGAAGACCCAGGAGGAACCCCCUGGCCAGAGCAGGGCCCCUGUGUUGACCGUGGUGUCCAAGUUCAAGGCCUCACUGGAGCAGCUUCUGCAGGUCCUACACAGCACCACGCCCCACUACAUUCGCUGCAUCAAGCCCAACAGCCAGGGCCAGGCGCAGACCUUUCUCCAAGAGGAGGUCCUGAGCCAGCUGGAGGCCUGUGGCCUCGUGGAGACCAUCCAUAUCAGUGCUGCUGGCUUCCCCAUCCGGGUCUCUCACCGAAACUUUGUAGAACGAUACAAGUUACUAAGAAGGCUUCAUCCUUGCACAUCCUCUGGCCCCGACAGCCCAUAUCCUGCCAAAGGGCUCCCUGAAUGGUGUCCACACAGCGAGGAAGCCACGCUUGAACCUCUCAUCCAGGACAUUCUCCACACUCUGCCGGUCCUAACUCAGGCAGCAGCCAUAACUGGUGACUCGGCUGAGGCCAUGCCAGCCCCCAUGCACUGUGGCAGGACCAAGGUGUUCAUGACUGACUCUAUGCUGGAGCUUCUGGAAUGUGGGCGUGCCCGGGUGCUGGAGCAGUGUGCCCGCUGCAUCCAGGGUGGCUGGAGGCGACACCGGCACCGAGAGCAGGAGCGGCAGUGGCGGGCCGUCAUGCUCAUCCAGGCAGCCAUUCGUUCCUGGUUAACUCGGAAACACAUCCAGAGGCUGCAUGCAGCUGCCACAGUCAUCAAGCGUGCAUGGCAGAAGUGGAGAAUCAGAAUGGCCUGCCUUGCUGCUAAAGAGCUGGAUGGUGUGGAAGAAAAACACUUCUCUCAAGCUCCCUGUUCCCUGAGCACCUCGCCGCUGCAGACCAGGCUCCUGGAGGCAAUAAUCCGCCUCUGGCCCCUGGGACUGGUCCUGGCCAAUACGGCUAUGGGUGUAGGCAGCUUUCAGAGGAAAUUAGUGGUCUGGGCUUGCCUCCAGCUCCCCAGGGGCAGCCCCAGUAGCUACACUGUCCAGACAGCACAAGACCAGGCUGGUGUCACGUCCAUCCGAGCGCUGCCUCAGGGAUCGAUAAAGUUUCACUGCAGAAAGUCUCCACUGCGGUAUGCUGACAUCUGCCCUGAACCUUCACCCUACAGCAUUACAGGCUUUAAUCAGAUUCUGCUGGAAAGACACAGGCUGAUCCACGUGACCUCUUCUGCCUUCACUGGGCUGGGGUGAUCCUUGGUGCCUUUGUUUCCACAAGGCCUUUUCCUGCCCCCUGCCUUGCCAAAGACAUUUAAUCAGCACACAGCUGCCAGACUAUUCCCACAGUGCUCCAAAUGCACAUGAACAACAGUGACGGCUCCAGCCUUCGACCCAGAGCCCCGUGCCCAGUGCGUCAGUGGGCCUGGGGUUCCAGGCUACAUCAAGCACUGAUGGUGUCAGGGCUGGUAGUUACCAAAUCAGGGUUAAGAAACAUCAGGGCCACAUUUCACUACCUUCACAGAUCAAACUCAGCAGCAGUCAUGACUGUCUGUCACUACACUGGGGAUCCCAAUUCCACAUAAGCACUUUUGGAAGAAAACAGCCAAAGUUGGCCUAAAAUUGGCGCUGGAAUUUGGGCUGGGAAAAAUCUUGUGGUUAUUUCCUUUAAAAAGGAACAAAACUUUAGUAUUUAAUUAGUUGAUUUAUUUAAUGUAAUUUCAAACAAUUAAAUUAUGAAUAAUGCAAUGUACAGUAGAAUCACGUUUUGAUUUUAUUAACACUGACCAAGUUUAACUCCAUAUGAAGUGUAAGCUUGAUAUCGUUUAUGAUGUCUAUCAACUGUACCAAAAGUAAAACAUUUAAAAACAA